UGUGCACGCACCCUCUCCCUCAUCCACCGCUGUCACCUCCUGCUGCUCUUCCUGCUGCUCGUGUACUCGUUAGGUGCGGACCCGCCACCUCUUUUGUGAAGCAGCAGCUGAGGAGACUCCGGUGUUCACCAUGGCCAACGAAAAGCCCACAGAAGAAGUCAAGACUGAGAACAACAAUCAUAUUAAUUUGAAGGUGGCGGGACAGGAUGGUUCUGUGGUGCAGUUUAAGAUUAAGAGGCAGACACCACUUAGUAAACUAAUGAAAGCCUAUUGUGAACCACGGGGAUUGUCAGUGAAGCAGAUCAGAUUCCGAUUUGGUGGGCAACCAAUCAGUGGAACAGACAAACCUGCACAGUUGGAAAUGGAAGAUGAAGAUACAAUUGAUGUGUUUCAACAGCCUACGGGAGGUGUCUACUGAAAAGGGAACCUGCUUCUUUACUCCAGAACGCUGUUCUUUAAAGACCAAGAUUACUGCAUUCUCAAUUAGAAAACUGCAAUUUGGUUCCACCACAUUCUGACUACUACAGUAUAGUUUUCUCUAUUCUUUUGUUUCCCCCUUCCACAUUCUUUUAUUAUACAUGAAGUAACUGGUAUGUGUACACAAGCAUAUUGCUUUUUUCUUCAAACCAAACAGCCAAUGGUAUGUUUUGAUUGACAUCAAGUGGAGACAGGAUGGGAAAAAAUACUGAUUCUGUGAAAAUACCCCCUUUAUCCAUUAGUGGCAUGUUCAUUCAGGUCUUAUCUUUAUAUUCUAGUAAGUUAUUUUGCUCUCACUGUUUUAACAACAACAAAAAAAAAUUCUCACAUACCUUGUUCAAUUGGAGGAUUUUCAUGUUUUUCAUUUAUCAUUGUAAAACCAAGGACAAUUUUAUAACUUUUGUGUACAUAGCUGUUACAUGUAGGGCAAUCUGUCUUUAAGUAGGGAUAAAUUACUCUAAAAAAAAAAGAAAGAAUCCUAGAAAGUUUUUCCUUCAAGUCAGGCUUCUUAUUUAAAUAAACUUUUUGUUUAAAAUGAAA